GCACAAGGCGCGUUCGAGCAGCGGCGACCGACGCGGCGAAGGAGCGCGCCAUGGAGCAUGUGACAGAGGGCUCCUGGGAGUCGCUGCCUGUGCCGCUGCACCCGCAGGUGCUGGGCGCGCUGCGGGAGCUGGGCUUCCCGUACAUGACGCCGGUGCAGGUUGGAGUGCAAUGACACGAUCUCGGCUCACUGCAACUUCUGCCUCCCGGGUUCAAGCUAUUCUCCCAUCUCAGCCUUCCAAGUAGCUGGGGUUACAGGCAUACACCACCACGCCUGGCUAAUUUUUGUGUUUUUAGUAGAGACGGGAUUUCGCCAUGUUGGCCAGACUGGUCUUGAACUCCUGACCUCAGGUACGCCCGCCUUGGCCUCCCAAAGUGCUGGGAUUACAGGAGUGAGCCACUGCGCCUGACCACAAGAGUCCUGUUUUUAAACACUGAGCUGGGUACAGUGGCACCCGCCUGUAGUACCAUUUGUUUGGAAGGCUGAGGUGGGAGGAUCCCUUGAGCCCAGGAGUUCAAGACCAGCCUGAGCAACAUAGUGAGACCCGCAUCUUCGAAAUUAAAAUAAAUAAUGGCCGGGCACGGUGGCUCACGCCUGUAAUCCUAGCACUUUUGGAGACCAAGGUGGGAGGAUCACUUGAGAUCAGGAGUUCAAGACCAGCCUGGGCAACAUAGGGAGGCCCUGUCAUCACAAAAAUUUUUUUUAAAUAAAUGAAGUCUUGAGUUUGAGAUGCCCAUAAGAUUCCCGGGAAUGUGGAGAAUGUAUUUCCAGCAGGCAGGGCUGGAGAUGAAAACUGGGAGUGCUAUGUGCCCUGCCUAGGGAAUGUAGUGCGAGCAAGACCCAAUCUCUGGCCUCAGAGCUCAUUGUCUAGACCUGUCAUCCACUACACAGUCAUCAGACAUGGCUAUCAAGUGCUUGAAAUACACUUUGUCCAAAUCAAAGUGUACUCUGAGUAUCAAAUAACACACUAGAUUUUGAAGACCUAGUAUGAAAAAAGAAUGGAAAAUGCUGAUUUUUAAAUAUUGACUAAAUGUGAAGGGACAAUAUUUUUGAUAUAUUGGGUUAAAUAAAAUAUUAAAAUUUAUUUCACCCAUUUCUUUUUACUUUUCUUACUAUGGCUAUUAGAAAAUUUAAAAUUGUUUAUGUGGUUCACAUUUUAUUUCUAUUGGACAGCAAUGGCCUGAAGCAGGGUCCUCACUGUUGGCACUAUUGACAUUUUGUGCUGGAAAAUUUUUUGUUAUGGGGCUGUCCUGGGCAUUGUAGGAUGUUUAACAACAUCACUGGAAUCUGUCCAUCAGAGGACAUCACCUCCCAACCCUGGUUGUAUUUUAUUUAUUUAUUUAUUUAUUGAGGCAGGGUUUUGCUCUGUUACCCGGGCUGGAGUGCAGUGGCACAGUCACAGCUCACAGUAGCCUCGACCUCCCUGGGCCUAGGUGAUCCUCUUACCUUAGCCUCCUGAGUAGCUGGGACUGCAGGCAUGCACCACCACACCCACAUAAUUAAAAAAAUUUUCUUUGUAGAGACAGAGUCUCCCUGUGUUGCCUGGCUGGUCUGGAAUUCCUGGCCUUAAGGGAUCUACCCACCUGGGCCUCCCAAAGUGCUGUGAUUAUAGAUGUGAGCCACCACGCCUGGCCCACCCUGGGUUUUGACAACCAAAAAUGUCUCCUUACAUUGUCAAAUGUUCCCUCAGGGGUUGAGCAGGGGGAUAGCAAUCACUGUGUAGAGGCAGUUAGAAUAAUAUUACACCUGCUGUGAUUUAAGUGAGCUCAGGCCCUGGGGACCAGGGCUGAAUCCUGGAGGGAGCAGCCUCCAGGCCAAGGCCUGAAUCUAAUUGAGGUUUUUUUUGAUUGCUAAAACCAGGUUUCUUUUAAAGUCUGGCAACCUCUACAGUGCUUAAAAUGAGAGGGUUUAUUUGAAUCAUGAUUCUGUGAUACUAGAGCUGGAAGGGACCCUAAAACCCAAUGUCUUCAACGCCUUCCUGGUUCAGAGAGGAAAGUAGGAGCGACAGGGCUAGAAUUCAGGACUCCCACCUCCCAGCUCAGCUCACUGUCCCCACACGCCGUCCACAUAGACACAGUUGCCACGUUUGAUUCAACUUCUCUAUGGUGACUUGGUUACUCAGAGCCCCUUUUGUGGUGGGACCCACUGUGACCUUAGCUGCCCAUUAUGUUCCUAGGGCUUCGGGUCUCACCUGUGAAUUGAUGGCAUCCUUUAACCAGUGCUUUGCAAUCUCUCUCUUUAGUCCGCAACCAUCCCUCUGUUCAUGCGAAACAAAGAUGUCGCUGCAGAAGCGGUCACAGGUAGUGGCAAAACACUCGCUUUUGUCAUCCCCAUCCUGGAAAUUCUUCUGAGAAGAGAAGAGAAGUUAAAAAAGAGUCAGGUUGGAGCCAUAAUCAUCACCCCCACUCGAGAGCUGGCCAUUCAAAUAGACGAGGUCCUGUCGCAUUUCACGAAGCACUUCCCCGAGUUCAGCCAGAUUCUUUGGAUCGGAGGCAGGAAUCCUGGAGAAGAUGUUGAGAGGUUUAAGCAACAAGGUGGGAACAUCAUUGUGGCCACUCCAGGCCGCUUGGAGGACAUGUUCCGGAGGAAGGCCGAAGGCUUGGAUCUGGCCAGCUGUGUGCGAUCCCUGGAUGUCCUGGUGUUGGAUGAGGCAGACAGACUUCUGGACAUGGGGUUUGAGGCAAGCAUCAACACCAUUCUGGAGUUUUUGCCAAAGCAGAGGAGAACAGGCCUUUUCUCUGCCACUCAGACGCAGGAAGUGGAGAACCUGGUGAGAGCGGGCCUCCGGAACCCUGUCCGGGUCUCAGUGAAGGAGAAGGGCGUGGCAGCCAGCAGUGCCCAGAAGACCCCCUCCCGCCUGGAAAACUACUACAUGGUAUGCAAGGCAGAUGAGAAAUUUAAUCAGCUGGUCCAUUUUCUUCGCAAUCAUAAGCAGGAGAAACACCUGGUCUUCUUCAGGUACUCCUCUGGUCUCUGUGGUAGAGGCAUCAGGGAUUCAGCCAGAAUGUGCAGCACCUGUGCCUGUGUGGAAUACUAUGGGAAGGCUCUGGAAGUGCUGGUGAAGGGCGUGAAGAUUAUGUGCAUUCACGGAAAGAUGAAAUAUAAACGCAAUAAGAUCUUCAUGGAGUUCCGCAAAUUGCAAAGUGGGAUUUUAGUGUGCACUGAUGUGAUGGCCCGGGGAAUUGAUAUUCCUGAAGUCAACUGGGUUUUGCAGUAUGACCCUCCCAGCAAUGCAAGUGCCUUCGUGCAUCGCUGCGGUCGCACAGCUCGCAUUGGCCACGGGGGCAGCGCUCUGGUGUUCCUCCUGCCCAUGGAAGAGUCAUACAUCAAUUUCCUUGCAAUUAACCAAAAAUGCCCCCUGCAGGAGAUGAAGCCCCAGAGAAACACAGCGGACCUUCUGCCAAAACUCAAGUCCAUGGCCCUGGCUGACAGAGCUGUGUUUGAAAAGGGCAUGAAAGCUUUUGUGUCAUAUGUCCAAGCUUAUGCAAAGCAUGAAUGCAACCUGAUUUUCAGAUUAAAGGAUCUUGAUUUUGCCAGCCUUGCUCGAGGUUUUGCCCUGCUGAGGAUGCCCAAGAUGCCAGAAUUGAGAGGAAAGCAGUUUCCAGAUUUUGUGCCCGUGGACGUUAAUACCGACACGAUUCCAUUUAAAGAUAAAAUCAGAGAAAAGCAGAGGCAGAAACUCCUGGAGCAACAAAGAAGAGAGAAAACAGAAAAUGAAGGGAGAAGAAAAUUCAUAAAAAAUAAAGCUUGGUCAAAGCAGAAGGCCAAAAAAGAAAAGAAGAAAAAAAUGAAUGAGAAAAGGAAAAGGGAAGAGGGUUCUGAUAUUGAAGAUGAGGACAUGGAAGAACUUCUUAAUGACACAAGACUCUUGAAAAAACUUAAGAAAGGCAAAAUAACUGAAGAAGAAUUUGAGAAGGGCUUGUUGACAACUGGCAAAAGAACAAUCAAGACAGUGGAUUUAGGGAUCUCAGAUUUGGAAGAUGACUGCUGAUUCCAGUGCCACAGAUGAACCCACAAGGACAUAGCUGUUCCCUAACUUGGUGGAUGGCUCCAGUUUGCUUUUAACGAAAAUCACAACUUCAGGAGACAUCUGAAAAGAAUGAUGUCUCUGAAAGCUGUCCUUUCAGAUGAGGGAGAAAUGAAGGAUUUCACACUUCAGAAUAUUUUACUAAAAACAUUCCAGUCUUGGCCGGGUGCGGUGGCUCCUGCCUAUAAUCCCAGCACUUUGGGAGGCUGAGGCAGGAGGAUCACUUGAGCCCAGGAGUUCAAGACCAGCCUGGGAACACAGCGAGACCCUCUCAUUAAAAACAACAAAACAAAACAAUUCCAGUCUUGGAGUAGUCUAACAGAAGAAAAUGUAAAAUUAUUUGAGUGUAAAUAAUAGAUGUCAGUAUUUAUCAUGAUGGGUCACAUAUAGACAUAUGUACAUAUU